AGUAAUAACCCCGGCGCGGCGGCGGAGUCGCUGUGGGGAAUCCUCCCGCGCUCUGCCUGGGUCGGGUCCUCCCUGCCCGCUCGCACGCUGCCGGCCGGGGACCCUCCGGUGGCCCCUAGCCCCUCGGAGCGCUCCUGGAUGAAGCCCCGCGCGCGCGGAUGGCGGGGCUUGGCGGCGCUGUGGAUGCUGUUGGCGCAGGUGGCCGAGCAGGCACCUGCGUGCGCCAUGGGACCCGCAGCGGCAGCGCCUGGGAGCCCGAGCGUCCCGCGUCCUCCUCCACCCGCGGAGCGGCCGGGCUGGAUGGAAAAGGGCGAAUAUGACCUGGUCUCUGCCUACGAGGUUGACCACAGGGGCGAUUACGUGUCCCAUGAAAUCAUGCACCAUCAGCGGCGGAGAAGAGCAGUGCCCGUGUCCGAGGUUGAGUCUCUUCACCUUCGGCUGAAAGGCUCCAGGCACGACUUCCACAUGGAUCUGAGGACUUCCAGCAGCCUAGUGGCUCCUGGCUUUAUUGUGCAGACGUUGGGAAAGACAGGCACUAAGUCUGUGCAGACUUUACCGCCAGAGGACUUCUGUUUCUAUCAAGGCUCUUUGCGAUCACACAGAAACUCCUCAGUGGCCCUUUCAACCUGCCAAGGCUUGUCAGGCAUGAUACGAACAGAAGAGGCAGAUUACUUCCUAAGGCCACUUCCUUCACACCUCUCAUGGAAACUCGGCAGAGCUGCCCAAGGCAGCUCGCCAUCCCACGUACUGUACAAGAGAUCCACAGAGCCCCAUGCUCCUGGGGCCAGUGAGGUCCUGGUGACCUCAAGGACAUGGGAGCUGGCACAUCAACCCCUGCACAGCAGCGACCUUCGCCUGGGACUGCCACAAAAGCAGCAUUUCUGUGGAAGACGCAAGAAAUACAUGCCCCAGCCUCCCAAGGAAGACCUCUUCAUCUUGCCAGAUGAGUAUAAGUCUUGCUUACGGCAUAAGCGCUCUCUUCUGAGGUCCCAUAGAAAUGAAGAACUGAACGUGGAGACCUUGGUGGUGGUCGACAAAAAGAUGAUGCAAAACCAUGGCCAUGAAAAUAUCACCACCUACGUGCUCACGAUACUCAACAUGGUAUCUGCUUUAUUCAAAGAUGGAACAAUAGGAGGAAACAUCAACAUUGCAAUUGUAGGUCUGAUUCUUCUAGAAGAUGAACAGCCAGGACUGGUGAUAAGUCACCACGCAGACCACACCUUAAGUAGCUUCUGCCAGUGGCAGUCUGGAUUGAUGGGGAAAGAUGGGACUCGUCAUGACCACGCCAUCUUACUGACUGGUCUGGAUAUAUGUUCCUGGAAGAAUGAGCCCUGUGACACUUUGGGAUUUGCACCCAUAAGUGGAAUGUGUAGUAAAUAUCGCAGCUGCACGAUUAAUGAAGAUACAGGUCUUGGACUGGCCUUCACCAUUGCCCAUGAGUCUGGACACAACUUUGGCAUGAUUCAUGAUGGAGAAGGGAACAUGUGCAAAAAGUCCGAGGGCAACAUCAUGUCCCCUACAUUGGCAGGACGCAAUGGAGUCUUCUCCUGGUCACCCUGCAGCCGCCAGUAUCUACACAAAUUUCUAAGCACCGCUCAAGCUAUCUGCCUUGCUGAUCAGCCAAAGCCUGUGAAGGAAUACAAGUAUCCUGAGAAAUUGCCAGGAGAAUUAUAUGAUGCAAACACACAGUGCAAGUGGCAGUUCGGAGAGAAAGCCAAGCUCUGCAUGCUGGACUUUAAAAAGGACAUCUGUAAAGCCCUGUGGUGCCAUCGUAUUGGAAGGAAAUGUGAGACUAAAUUUAUGCCAGCAGCAGAAGGCACAAUUUGUGGGCAUGACAUGUGGUGCCGGGGAGGACAGUGUGUGAAAUAUGGUGAUGAAGGCCCCAAGCCCACCCAUGGCCACUGGUCGGACUGGUCUUCUUGGUCCCCAUGCUCCAGGACCUGCGGAGGGGGAGUAUCUCAUAGGAGUCGCCUCUGCACCAACCCCAAGCCAUCGCAUGGAGGGAAGUUCUGUGAGGGCUCCACUCGCACUCUGAAGCUCUGCAACAGUCAGAAAUGUCCCCGGGACAGUGUUGACUUCCGUGCUGCUCAGUGUGCCGAGCACAACAGCAGACGAUUCAGAGGGCGGCACUACAAGUGGAAGCCUUACACUCAAGUAGAAGAUCAGGACUUAUGCAAACUCUACUGUAUCGCAGAAGGAUUUGAUUUCUUCUUUUCUUUGUCAAAUAAAGUCAAAGAUGGGACUCCAUGCUCGGAGGAUAGCCGUAAUGUUUGUAUAGAUGGGAUAUGUGAGAGAGUUGGAUGUGACAAUGUCCUUGGAUCUGAUGCUGUUGAAGACGUCUGUGGGGUGUGUAACGGGAAUAACUCAGCCUGCACGAUUCACAGGGGUCUCUACACCAAGCACCACCACACCAACCAGUAUUAUCACAUGGUCACCAUUCCUUCUGGAGCCCGGAGUAUCCGCAUCUAUGAAAUGAACGUCUCUACCUCCUACAUUUCUGUGCGCAAUGCCCUCAGAAGGUACUACCUGAAUGGGCACUGGACCGUGGACUGGCCCGGCCGGUACAAAUUUUCGGGCACUACUUUCGACUACAGACGGUCCUAUAAUGAGCCCGAGAACUUAAUCGCUACUGGACCAACCAACGAGACACUGAUUGUGGAGCUGCUGUUUCAGGGAAGGAACCCGGGUGUUGCCUGGGAAUACUCCAUGCCUCGCUUGGGGACCGAGAAGCAGCCCCCUGCCCAGCCCAGCUACACUUGGGCCAUCGUGCGCUCUGAGUGCUCCGUGUCCUGCGGAGGGGGACAGAUGACCGUGAGAGAGGGCUGCUACAGAGACCUGAAGUUUCAAGUAAAUAUGUCCUUCUGCAAUCCCAAGACACGACCUGUCACGGGGCUGGUGCCUUGCAAAGUAUCUGCCUGUCCUCCCAGCUGGUCCGUGGGGAACUGGAGUGCCUGCAGUCGGACGUGUGGCGGGGGUGCCCAGAGCCGCCCCGUGCAGUGCACACGGCGGGUGCACUAUGACUCGGAGCCAGUCCCGGCCAGCCUGUGCCCUCAGCCUGCUCCCUCCAGCAGGCAGGCCUGCAACUCUCAGAGCUGCCCACCUGCAUGGAGCGCCGGGCCCUGGGCAGAGGUAACCAGGGUGGGGUUGGCAUGGGUGGCAGCAGGGCCCCUGCAUGAUCUGCUGUGUUGCACAUGGCCCUCACUGGGUGCUUAUCCUGACUGUUCUGUGCAGUGCUCACACACCUGUGGGAAGGGGUGGAGGAAGCGGGCAGUGGCCUGUAAGAGCACCAACCCCUCGGCCAGAGCGCAGCUGCUGCCCGACGCUGUCUGCACCUCCGAGCCCAAGCCCAGGAUGCAUGAAGCCUGUCUGCUUCAGCGCUGCCACAAGCCCAAGAAGCUGCAGUGGCUGGUGUCCGCCUGGUCCCAGUGCUCUGUGACAUGUGAAAGAGGAACACAGAAAAGAUUCUUAAAAUGUGCUGAAAAGUAUGUUUCUGGAAAGUAUCGAGAGCUGGCCUCAAAGAAGUGCUCACAUUUGCCGAAGCCCAGCCUGGAGCUGGAACGUGCCUGCGCCCCGCUUCCAUGCCCCAGGCACCCCCCAUUUGCUGCUGCGGGACCCUCGAGGGGCAGCUGGUUUGCCUCACCCUGGUCUCAGUGCACGGCCAGCUGUGGGGGAGGCGUUCAGACGAGGUCCGUGCAGUGCCUGGCUGGGGGCCGGCCGGCCUCAGGCUGCCUCCUGCACCAGAAGCCUUCGGCCUCCCUGGCCUGCAACACUCACUUCUGCCCCAUUGCAGAGAAGAAAGAUGCCUUCUGCAAAGACUACUUCCACUGGUGCUACCUGGUACCCCAGCACGGGAUGUGCAGCCACAAGUUCUACGGCAAGCAGUGCUGCAAGACUUGCUCUAAGUCCAACUUGUGAGUUGGGACCGCUCUCCGUAGCAGAGAAAGUGCCUGCGUGGCACAGAAAUUUCCCACAAAUGAGCUGUGCAAUCUACGUCGGAAUACAUCCAAGGAAGAGCAAAGCCAAAAGAAGAAAACCGUGUUAGGCUCUUUGACCAGGAGUGUAUGUAUGUGUUUCACUGUGAGCCUGGGUGCAGACCUGUGUCCCCAUGCACACAGUGUCUCCUGUCAGGCUGAAAUGUGGCACCCUGGCAGACAGAGCUGUGGCUCGUGAGGCAGAAGGCAGGCACCACAACGGGAGAGGCAGCACUCACCCCUGCCUGUUGCAGCUAAAUCAAGUCAAAAAGACAGGCGAGGCUGAACUUGCUAAAUGUCUGGUGCCUUAGAAAAAGAAGGAAAGGCCAUGAAAUAAGGAAAACAUACAAAAUAUGUACCCCCUAGUUCACCAGCCUCCCCUCCCACUAGGAGGGCCCCUCGAGCCAUCAGGAGUGACCAACUUCCUGGGUGGAGGUCAGGGGAGCUCCAGGAGGCUGCCCAGGCUCCUCCUCCUCCUCCCCAGCGGCCGAGCAUCUCUUACCAGGAACCUGGAGCCACCGCCGGAGCCAGCGUCAUCUCUAGGGUCACUGGCCAGGGGACUGCAUUCUGGUUUGGGACUUUGCCUAUGGAAAUGGGAAAAAUGAAAUUCCUGCUAAGGUGCUUCUAUCUCUUUCAGAUUCAUGCAUUGAAGGAGAGAUUUUUUAUACUUUAUGUUUUAUCUUUCUCAGUUAUUUGCAAGUGAGUGUCCUUUUAAAAACACACUUCUUCAUGCUUUUCUUUGUAAAUGACAGAUCGAAGUAUAGGUUACAUCAAAACCCUACCAUCCUGAGAAGAGUUAUGGUUCUAUUAUAGCAGACGUCAGCCACACAGCCUAUGUGACAAUAACCUUAGAGUCCUGUGUUUUGUUUUUGUGUGUUGUGAGAUUUUAAUCUUUUUUUUUUCGGUGAGUCUGGCCAUUUCUAUAAUGCCAGGUGGGAAGCCAGGCUGCGGGUGUUAGGGUGGGAAUCUGCCCGGCGUCUCUGGCACCCUCCCUGCCAUCCUCAGUGCGGCUGCUGUUCUCCUGUCCGGUGCUGUGGCUCCAUUCCAAAGGGGCACCUGGAUAUUUAUAUUUGCUGAAGUUUUAUAAUAAAGUUUAUAUGGUACAGUGUG